GCUGGGAUUACAGGCGUGAGCCACCGCUCCCGGAAGUAUUCAAACUUUCAUCCAUUAGUUUGGGUACCCAUUGAUUCUUCCCUGAGUGGAUGAUGAUGAAGAUGAUGAUGGUUAUCAAAUGGUGAUUUUCUAACUCCAUACUCUUUUUCUACGUUUAUUAGUUGAGUUUCUACCCUGUGGAAGAACUUUCCUUUCUCCCACACUUUUUUUUUUCUUAAAGUAGGGACUUGGGGAUUGUUAUGUUACACAUUGGGUUGCAAUCACUUACUGUCACUUAAUUUUCUUGCUCACGUUGUCCCUGAUGUGGCCACUGGGAGCCCCUCCAACCCACUCCUAGGUCAUUUUGACACAUCUUCCUUAUUCUUUGAGCACAAGUAGAUGCUCCGAGCUCAUCUUGAACUUUUCCUGCUCCAGCCCAAGAAUUGGCCAUGUCUCCAAGGAGCCCCAGUUCCAUUUUGUGGAGAAUGGUUACACCAGACACGUCUUAAACUAAGAGAAAAAAAGAAAAGGAAUGGAUUCAGGGAUCCUCUUUUUUCCUAUUUCCCCCAUUGUUUUAUUAAGCACCUAUUACAUGUCAGAUGUGGAGGACUCAGAGAUGAAUAGCACAGGGAACCUGAUCUCAUGCCACUCAUAGCCUUGUGGUGGGGACAGACAAGCCCAUAGAUAACACCCAGGAAUGAGAAGAAUCUUCACCUUUCAUAGGCUGCCUGAUACAGCCCCCUGGCCAUAGCACAAUCCCCUUCUCCAUUCUUGAAGCCACAGAGUGCAGUAUUUCACAGCAUAAACAUUCCAUUUGGGAACUGUGAUAAUCUUGAGAAAGAUUUUCAUUUAUAGUGACCCCACCUCUCUUUCCUUAUAGAUUCCCCUCAUUGCCCCUAAUUCAACCCUGGAACUAGGUGGAACCCAUAGAACCAAACCCACUUGCCUGUGGCAGGCAGGGUUUCAUAUAGCCGAGGAUAGCUGCCUUGCCCUGCAACGGGACUUCUCUUCCCUGCACCCGUGAAUGGUGUGUGUGUUCAGCCAUUCCGAUGAGGCUACAGCUUCUUUGUUGGUAUCUCUCUUAGGAGAUUCCCUGGAGUGGUUCCUAACAUUAUUCACGCAGACAGAGAAAGUGAUGGGCUGUGGACCUGCUGAGCUCCAACAGGUACAGAGUAGUACUGUUGCCAAAGGCCCCAUUAUGGUCUUUGGCCACCAUGCCAACUUCGGGCUUCCUCUGAGUUUGUCAUCAAGUAAAACUCCUAGAUAUUUUGUUAUUGUUGUUUGCAUGAACUCUUAUGACUCCAAGUCUCUUCCAUCCUCUAUUGGUUUAGCAGAUUGCCUGAAGUUAAAUGUAGGGCUUCAUGUUUUUCCAUCUAAAGUUUUGUUCUGUUAGUUUGGGCCUGUUGUUCCAACUCAUGGAGAUUUUUUUCCUCAGUCUUGAUUCCACCGUUGAGCAUUUUAAUUGUUCCCUCGAGUCUGGUGUGCUCUGCAAGUGGACAUGCCUGCAUGGUCUUGUUCCUCAAGCUGUUGAUUUCAGUCAGCCAAAUAGGGACAAGACAGAGCCUUGUUGGCGUGUCCCGAGACACACGGACCUCUGUGUUGACGCUUAAAAUAAUGGCAUCAUUAGUCGGCUAUAAAAUUGGCCACAGUUUAUUAUCUGAAAGCCAUUUUGCCAUCCUGGAUAUAAAGAAAUGAUAAAUUUUGUGCUACCUUAUUAAGAUAAAAAAGCAGACUUUAUUGUAUUUCUCAGAUCAUUAAGUCUAAGUAAGGGUAUUUUUCGGUUUAUUUUAUGUGGGUUUUCUUACUGGACCUACAGCUAAUCGCUAAUUCCUCAGGAUCAUCCCACCCCUAAAAUUCUUUUCCAGCAACUUGAAUCUGUUUGAAAACUAUGAAGAACUUACAGUAUAUGCUUUACAACAUAUUCUUGAAGUAUUUCCAUAUCCAUUAAGUCACUCUGACAUUGUGACUUUCUCCAAAACGAUGCACACACAUCACUCUUUCCCCUUCUCUUGUUUUAUAUUACUUUAUAUUGCUUUUUAUUUGAGUGUAUUUGUGUGUGGUCUCUCUUCUCUACAAGAAUGUAAGCCGAGACCUUUUAGCAUGGAUUCUGUAGCAUCUGACUGACACAUAGUACAUGCUCAGUAAAUGCUGAACGAAUGAAUAUGUUUCCUGAUCUGUAGGUUCUGGAACCUGCCUUUUGUCCUUCUUUAAAAAUCAGGAUAUUGGACCUACAUUUCAGUUCUUUGCAGCAGCUUCUCCUACCUCCUUUAUCCUCUCUUGUCUGCCUAAAGAUAUCCAAGCAAAUCAGUCUGCUUUGAACUGUUCCCCUCACCCCCAUCACUCUCAAGCAAGAAAAGGGCGUUUGGGUGAGAUGCCAGCGUUCUUUUGCAUGAGCAGUCCUGGGAUCCCAUCACCUUAGGACAGUCCCUGGGUGCUUAAAGACUGAGUGUGAAUGUGAGAUGUAGGGAUGUUCUAGUGUUCUCUUUUGAAAAUUAGACAUUAAAGAAAAACAGGCCAGGUGCGGUGGCUCACGCCUGUAAUCCCAGCACUUUGGGAGGCCGAGGCGGGCAGAUUGCCUGAGCUCAGGAGUUUGAGACCAGCCUGGCCAACAUGGUGAAACCCCAUCUAUACUAAAACUACAAAAAGUUAGCCAGACGUGGUGGUGGUCGCCUGUAGGCCCAGCUACUCAGGAGGGUGAGGCAGGAGAAUCGCUUGAGCCCAAGAGGCAGAGGUUGCAGUGAGCUGAGAUCGCACCACUGCACUCCAGCCUGGGUGACAAAGGAAAACUGCCUGAAAGCAUAGACUCCACACCCAUACUCUCCGGUUUGUCAGUCAGGCUGCAUAACUGGGCCACCUCAGUUUUCCCAUUUCUAAAAUGGGGAUAAAAAUAGUAUCUAUCUCCUAGUGUGGGUAUGAGGAUCAAAGUGAUGCUGUACCCAUGGGUCUUAACACAACACCUAACUCAUUAAGUGAUGACUUCCAGUAUGAUGGUUUUCAAUUUUUUUCCUUUUUUUUUUUUUUUAAAUAGACCAAGUCUCAUUUUGUCACCCAGGCUGGAAUGCAGUGGCCCGAUCGUAGCUCACUGCAGCCUUGAACUCCUGGGCUCUAGCAAUCCUACUGUCUCAAUGAUGGUUUUAAUUUUAAAGAGCUUUGGGAAAUAAAGGCACAUAGGAGGAAAUGAAGUCACCUAUACCUCAUUCCCUAGAAUUCACAGUUGUAAAAAUUGUAAUAUAAGUCUCUCCUGUUUUCCUCUCCAUAAUACCUAUAUGUGCUGUGUUCAUUUAGCAUCUGUAUGAUCAUUUUCCCAUGCUUAUAAAUAGUUUCUUUGAAGAAAGCAUCUUUAUAACAACAUAUGGAGCUCUGUGCACUGUAAUUUAUUUAGGGUCUGUUUUUGCCCAAAUUUUUCCUCUUUUUUCCUGUUAUGUUUUUCAUGAAUAAACUUAAAUCUCCAUGCAUUGCUUGGGUUCUUUCCUUAUGAUGAAUUCCUAGAACGGGGAAUUGUUGAGUCAACGGGGAGGGAUGUGCACUUCUGAGGCCUUUGAUGUAUGCUGCCUGGUCGCCUGUAGGAAGGCGGUAUUCACUGCUUCUCCCUCCGGCAGAGCAGGGGAUCACCCAGGGAAUCAGGCAUCCUUGCCUGCUGGCUGAUGUCUCUUGAGUGAUCCCGCAUGGGAUAUUCUUGGAGGCAACAGUUUCUCACUGCCUCUAUUCUCUCUUUGUUUUUCCUCCCUUCCCCUUUGUUUCCCUUCUUGGUUUCCUACCAGACAGCCUCUUGUGAAAGGACUGCCUAAUUAACCCUGUGCUAAUUAACAAUUUAAAAUUACACAGUGCGACUGUUCAUGUUUCAUUCUCCGGGAGCUGGAGCAACAGCAGGAGCCCCCUCCCCUUCGUCAUAACUGCACCCCUCCCACCCCAGCUUCCCUGAAACUGUUGCAUUUUACCCAGUUCUGCCUCAAGGGAACAGGAUAAAACUGUCAUCAGCACAUGUUUUUAAAGAGGGAGAUGAACGUUUUGAUUAAUAGGGAGAUACAGGGUAACAGGGUAGAGUUUUAUCCUUUUAAACAAUCUUUGAAAAGUAAAGAUUGACAUUUGCAAAGAUGCAGUGGGCUUUACAGGUGGUUCCAAGGGAGCUUGGAAGAUGAGCAGGAGUUGGGGGAUACUUGAUGAAGGUGCUGGAAUUCUUCUGUACAAGAUUACCUUUCAGAUGGCAGAUUUAAGUGCUAAGCAGACAGUGAGCCAGCUAGGUCAUUCCUAUCUUCCCUUUAACUUUCUCACUGGAGAGAUGUGCUCUAUUAAAAUCUAACUGAAUUCUUGAAGCCCAUAUGUUGAGUGCAACAUUGGGGGUUGUGAGCAGAAUACCUGGACAUUUUUUAGAGGGAGUUCCGGGUGCCACCAGCAGAGAAGCGGGCUGCAGGAAGGGAGGAGGGGUGUGAACCUGUACCAGCUAGCCCUGGCACUAGGGAAGUACUGGGAAGGGGCACAGAACGUGGAGGGAGCCUGAAGAGAGGUGUGCGUGUCAGGCUGGCAGGGCUGCUUGGAAAAGUGCGGGGACCCACUGGGUUCCCAGGCUGCCCUCUGUAACUGAAGAUCAUUGAUUUUACGGGAAACCGUGUUUACAGACAGAGUGCUGAUCGACCUGCCGAGUUGACUUCUGCCUCCUUAAGUAAGAACUACCUUUUUCUUAUUGACUGGCUGAUAAACAGAGCGAGAGAGAGCCGGCUGUUGCGGGGGAGUGGUAGAUGCCCUGAGACCCUUGAGCCACAGGAUGUGGCGGAUUGGGGAGACUUCUUUACCUCUGUGCGCGCGUCCCCCUCUUCUCCAUCUCCAUCCCUGCACCUCCCAGGGACCACAGGGAAUCUAAGACUGACCUUCCCUGGUUACCUAGCAAUACAGGUACCAAGGACAGAAGAGCUGUGCUUGGUACCUGUAUUGGUGAAGAUGGAGUGAAGCAGAGAGUGUCUUAAGUUUAAUGCAUGGUCCCUGAGGAUGGUGUGAAAAUGCAGAUUCUGAUGGGGCAGGAGGAGACAGUGCAUGUCUCUUAAGCUCCCCGGAGAGGAUAAUGCUUCAAGUCCACAAACCACGCUUGUUUGGCAAGGCUGCAAACGGGCCUGUUUGUCACAGCUGGUGCGCAUGGAAAGGAGGCCCAGGGGAGGUAGCUUGGGUCCUGCAGUGGGUUCCUCCUCUCCGACCCGUGUCCUCAUGGCUGCUGCUCCCCGUGAAUGGGUGGGCUCUAGUGUCACCACCACAGGGUCACCAGCCACCAUCAUAGGUGGGUACAGUGUCAUUCUUUCCUGACAUCUUCCGCUUUGGAGUAGAAAACAAAGUAAGGGAGGUUUUAAAAGUCCCAGCCUCUUGGCUGGAUAGUUUGUGGAAGAGGAGGAGGAAUAAGAGGAGAACGGAGCAAGAGAAGCCCACCAAUUAAUUGGUAAACGCUUGCAGGUUUCUCUGGCCCAGCCCAGGCUGGAGAGGAGAUUGGCUUUGCUGUCGAUAAACAAGUCCCUGGUGCAGCAUCAAAGCUGUUCUGCUUUAUCAAUCGUGGCCCCCCCUUCCCGCAUGUUCCUGUAACUUACCAAGCAUUUAUGACAUUGAUUUUACAAUCGGGCUGUUAACCCUCCCGCCCCUUCAGGCCUGCCAACCUUUUUGGCCCAAGCUAUCAAUCAGAUGUCAUCCAGCCAAUCAGAAGCAUCCCUAAGAAGAGCCGCCCUGCAGUCUCACCUGUAUCCCGGCUCAGCCUUGCGAGGAAGUCCCAUUGCGUUUGCUGUUUGGUUUGGUUUGGUUUGGUUUGGUUUGGUUUGGUUUGGUUUGGUUUACUGUAGUCAUCUCUGUUUUAAGUCAGUAUGUCCUUUCUAAGGCUCAUGGAACUUUGUGGUUGCAAAAUCUGAAGUUAUAAAUGGAGAGAUAGGGGUAUGUGUUUGCAUGUGUGUAUUAGACACAUCAUAGCUUUAUUCUUCCAAAAAGUUAUUUCUCCCUGAGACUUCUGGUAAACCUGCCUUCCCCAGUUUUUCCCGAGGGGGAGCUGUUGUCUCAUUGUGCAGUCAAUAAUCAAGAAAUGAAAAAAAAAAAAGAUUGAGAAGAUAGGGGCUGUCAGGGAGGGAAGUGAGAUCAAACCUGGCCGAAACCUUCACCGGCUGAGUGUGAAUGAGAUGGUGGGUGGAGGAGCAGCCACAUGUUCUCCAGGAGGAGCAGCAGGGGAAUGGUGGCUGGGGACCUACGGGCAAAGGAUCAGGGCUCUGCGAGGUGCUGAGCUGCCUGUAGGAGCAGGGCCAGACGGAAUGAUCGCCCCUGCGAUGAUAUUACUGCAGGAGCAGAGCGGCCGUGAUCCGAUGCCUCCCUCCCCAGGGACAUGAGGUCUCAGAGGGCACAUUCAGCUCAGUGGCACUUUGGAGUCGGAAAUGGAAAAGCCCCAGGGCUGAACGACAGCUGGUUGGGUAGCGACUAAUAACUAAGAGGCAGGUGUGGAGCUGGGGCUCGCCGAGCCCAGCUGCCGUCUCGGCUUGCUGCUCAGAUCCUUGAUAGCAAAAACCACCAGGCACGUGGGGAACGCACUCCCUCCAGCCAGGGCCAGAUAGAAGCUGCUGGAGGGGGUGUUGGCAGAUCCAGAGUCUGGUCCAUUCCUGCUGGAAAUACCAAGCUCACGUUUUGCACCUACGUAGUUUUAGUCUGAAGUCAGCUAGAGUCACAGGCCAGGGAGCUUGACUGGUAUGGGUGGAGGAGACAGGAAUCUGGGGACCCAUCUUUUCUUCUGUUUCAUGGUGGUGAGAUUAGCACUGAGCCAGUUUUUAGAUUGAAGCCCCUCUGUUUUACUGCUUGUAAAAUGGGACUGACGCCUCCCAGAUCUGGAGAGGACUUUUCGGAGUGUGUCUAGUCCUGUACACCUGCCCUGUGAACCUCAGGGUCCUCACCCGCCUUCUUUGAACUUCUCAAACUAGAACCAUGGUCAGUAAAAGCGACGGCUGCAAUUGUUCUAAAUCCAUGAGCGUUAUCCCACUUUACCGUCCUUUUUCCAGGGACAUUGAACCUCCCUCUUCUCAGCCCUCCCCUGUGUUCCCCUGACCCACAGACAGUGCGCGGAGUCGGGGCUGACUUCGUGUGAGCUGUCCAUAAGUGGUAGGGCUGUGGCUGUGACCUCGUAGAGGGCUGGAGAGAUGACGCGUCCGUUCUCCACUGUGGCCCAUCGAAGCUAUGCUGGCAAAGAAUGGAAAUUCCCGCUAGUCUUCAGGGGCAGAGCGGUGACAAUUCGAAGCCGAAGAGGGCUGUUCCUGGCCUUCUUUCCCCAUAUCCCUCGCUCAGGCUGUUGACCCGGCCAUGCCACCCCUGUGUGCUGGACCGUGUGGGGCAGUGUCCCCAGGCCCGCCCUCCGCCCUGUGUCUCUGUGUUGUGGACAGAAGCCUCUUAGAGCGCUCCGUGCGGUAGGACCUCAGCCUCGGCCCUCCUAACCUCUUUCCUUUCUCUCUCUCUUUCCCCUCUCUCCCUCCUCCCCCCUUGCCUCUGCCCUUCAGGUCCGAGCCUCCGUACUGGGUGCAAUGAAAGCUCCACGCAGGCCUUACCAUGGAAGGCUGUGACUCGCCCGUCGUCUCGGGGAAGGACAAUGGGUGCGGUAUCCCUCAGCACCAGCAAUGGACUGAACUCAACAGCACCCACCUCCCUGACAAACCCAGUAGCAUGGAGCAGUCCACAGGCGAGAGCCACGGGCCCUUGGACAGCCUGAGGGCCCCCUUCAAUGAGCGCCUCGCGGAGAGCACCGCGUCGGCCGGGCCCCCCUCCGAGCCCGCCAGCAAGGAGGUCACCUGCAACGAAUGUUCGGCCUCCUUUGCCAGCCUCCAGACCUACAUGGAGCACCACUGCCCCAGCGCGCGCCCCCCGCCACCCCUGAGAGAGGAGAGCGCCAGCGACACCGGUGAGGAGGGGGACGAGGAGAGUGACGUGGAGAACCUGGCCGGGGAGAUCGUCUACCAGCCGGACGGCUCCGCGUACAUUGUGGAGAGCCUGAGCCAGCUGACCCAGGGCGGGGGCGCCUGUGGGAGUGGCAGUGGCAGUGGGCCUCUCCCCUCGCUUUUCCUGAACUCUCUCCCUGGCGCGGGGGGCAAGCAAGGGGACCCUUCGUGUGCUGCACCCGUGUACCCGCAGAUCAUCAACACUUUCCACAUAGCCUCAUCCUUCGGGAAAUGGUUUGAGGGCCCAGACCAGGCUUUCCCGAAUACCUCAGCCCUGGCGGGGCUCAGCCCCGUCCUGCACAGCUUCCGCGUGUUUGACGUGCGACACAAAAGCAACAAGGAUUACCUGAACAGCGACGGUUCUGCCAAAAGCUCCUGCGUAUCCAAAGAUGUUCCCAACAAUGUGGACCUGUCCAAAUUCGAUGGCUUUGUGCUCUAUGGCAAGAGGAAGCCCAUCCUGAUGUGUUUCUUGUGCAAACUCUCCUUUGGGUACGUCCGUUCGUUUGUGACCCACGCGGUGCAUGACCAUCGAAUGACCCUGAGCGAAGACGAGCGGAAAAUUCUUAGCAAUAAGAACAUCUCCGCUAUCAUCCAAGGGAUCGGCAAAGACAAGGAACCCCUUGUAAGUUUUCUGGAACCAAAAAACAAAAACUUUCAACACCCUUUAGUUUCCACAGCUAACCUCAUAGGCCCCGGACACAGUUUUUAUGGUAAAUUUAGUGGCAUUCGAAUGGAAGGGGAGGAAGCUCUCCCAGCGGGCUCCGCCGCUGGCCCCGAGCAGCCCCAGGCUGGUCUCUUGACCCCCAGCACCCUGUUGAACCUUGGCGGGCUCACCAGCUCGGUACUGAAGACCCCCAUUACCUCAGUCCCCCUGGGGCCUCUGGCUUCCAGUCCUACCAAAUCCUCAGAGGGCAAGGACUCUGGGGCGGCAGAAGGAGAGAAGCAGGAAGUGGGCGACGGGGAUUGCUUCUCUGAGAAGGUAGAGCCAGCCGAAGAGGAGGCGGAGGAGGAAGAGGAGGAGGAAGAGGCGGAGGAGGAGGAGGAAGAAGAGGAGGAGGAAGAAGAGGAGGAGGAAGACGAGGGUUGCAAAGGACUCUUUCCAAGCGAGUUGGAUGAGGAACUGGAGGACAGGCCCCAUGAGGAGCCUGGGGCCGCAGCAGGUAGUAGCAGCAAAAAGGACCUUGCUCUCUCAAACCAAAGCAUUUCUAACUCCCCCUUAAUGCCUAACGUGCUCCAGACCCUGUCGAGGGGCACAGCUUCUACUAGUUCUAAUUCUGCUUCUUCCUUUGUUGUCUUUGAUGGUGCGAACAGGAGGAAUCGUUUAAGCUUUAACAGUGAGGGCGUCAGGGCCAAUGUGGCAGAGGGCGGCAGGAGGCUGGACUUCGCUGACGAAAGUGCCAAUAAAGACAAUGCCACAGCACCAGAACCAAAUGAAAGCACAGAGGGUGACGAUGGGGGCUUCGUUCCCCAUCACCAGCACGCUGGCUCCCUCUGCGAGCUUGGGGUUGGGGAGUGCCCCUCGGGGAGUGGCGUGGAGUGCCCCAAAUGCGACACGGUCCUGGGCUCCUCCCGCUCGCUGGGCGGCCACAUGACCAUGAUGCAUUCUCGUAACUCGUGUAAGACACUCAAGUGCCCCAAGUGCAACUGGCACUAUAAGUACCAGCAGACCCUGGAGGCACACAUGAAGGAGAAGCACCCGGAGCCGGGGGGCUCCUGUGUCUACUGCAAAAGCGGGCAGCCCCACCCCCGGCUGGCACGAGGCGAGAGCUACACGUGUGGUUACAAGCCUUUCCGCUGCGAGGUGUGUAACUACUCCACAACUACCAAAGGCAACCUCAGUAUUCAUAUGCAGUCUGACAAGCAUCUCAACAACAUGCAGAACCUGCAGAAUGGAGGGGGGGAGCAGGUCUUCAGCCACACUGCCGGGGCGGCGGCGGCGGCGGUGGCUGCGGCGGCGGCGGCAGCCAAUAUCAGUAGCUCCUGCGGGGCCCCCUCGCCGACCAAACCAAAAACCAAACCCACCUGGCGGUGCGAGGUGUGUGAUUAUGAGACCAACGUGGCCAGGAACCUCCGCAUUCACAUGACCAGUGAGAAGCACAUGCAUAACAUGAUGUUACUGCAACAGAACAUGACCCAGAUCCAACACAACCGCCACCUGGGCCUCGGCAGCCUGCCCUCACCCGCCGAGGCCGAGCUCUACCAAUACUACCUGGCCCAGAACAUGAACCUGCCCAACCUGAAGAUGGACAGUGCUGCCUCGGACGCCCAGUUCAUGAUGAGCGGAUUCCAGCUGGAUCCCGCCGGGCCCAUGGCCGCCAUGACGCCUGCUCUAGUGGGCGGUGAGAUCCCCCUAGACAUGCGGCUCGGGGGCGGGCAGCUGGUGUCAGAGGAGCUGAUGAACCUGGGCGAGAGCUUCAUCCAGACCAACGACCCGUCGCUGAAGCUCUUCCAGUGCGCCGUCUGCAACAAGUUCACGACGGACAACCUGGACAUGCUGGGCCUGCACAUGAACGUGGAGCGCAGCCUGUCGGAGGACGAGUGGAAGGCGGUGAUGGGGGACUCAUACCAGUGCAAGCUCUGCCGCUACAACACCCAGCUCAAGGCCAACUUCCAGCUGCACUGCAAGACAGACAAGCACGUGCAGAAGUACCAGCUGGUGGCCCACAUCAAGGAGGGCGGCAAGGCCAACGAGUGGAGGCUCAAGUGUGUGGCCAUCGGCAACCCCGUGCACCUCAAGUGCAACGCCUGUGACUACUACACCAACAGCCUGGAGAAGCUGCGGCUGCACACGGUCAACUCCAGGCACGAGGCCAGCCUGAAGUUGUACAAGCACCUGCAGCAGCAUGAGAGUGGUGUAGAAGGUGAGAGCUGCUACUACCACUGCGUUCUGUGCAACUACUCCACCAAGGCCAAGCUCAACCUCAUCCAGCAUGUGCGCUCCAUGAAGCACCAGCGAAGCGAGAGCCUGCGAAAGCUGCAGCGGCUGCAGAAGGGCCUUCCAGAGGAGGACGAGGACCUGGGGCAGAUCUUCACCAUCCGCAGGUGCCCCUCCACGGACCCAGAAGCCAUUGAAGAUGUUGAAGGACCCAGUGAAACAGCUGCUGAUCCAGAGGAGCUUGCUAAGGACCAAGAGGGCGGAGCAUCGUCCAGCCAAGCAGAGAAGGAGCUGACAGAUUCUCCUGCAACCUCCAAACGCAUCUCCUUCCCAGGUAGCUCAGAGUCUCCCCUCUCUUCGAAGCGACCAAAAACAGCUGAGGAGAUCAAACCGGAGCAGAUGUACCAGUGUCCCUACUGCAAGUACAGUAAUGCCGAUGUCAACCGGCUCCGGGUGCAUGCCAUGACGCAGCACUCGGUGCAACCCAUGCUUCGCUGCCCCCUGUGCCAGGACAUGCUCAACAACAAGAUCCACCUCCAGCUGCACCUCACCCACCUCCACAGCGUGGCACCUGACUGCGUGGAGAAGCUCAUUAUGACGGUGACCACCCCUGAGAUGGUGAUGCCAAGCAGCAUGUUCCUCCCAGCAGCUGUUCCAGAUCGAGAUGGGAAUUCCAAUUUGGAAGAGGCAGGAAAGCAGCCUGAAACCUCAGAGGAUCUGGGAAAGAACAUCUUGCCAUCCGCAAGCACAGAGCAAAGCGGAGAUUUGAAACCAUCCCCUGCUGACCCAGGCUCUGUGAGAGAAGACUCAGGCUUCAUCUGCUGGAAGAAGGGGUGCAACCAGGUUUUCAAAACUUCUGCUGCCCUUCAGACGCAUUUUAAUGAAGUGCAUGCCAAGAGGCCUCAGCUGCCGGUGUCAGAUCGCCAUGUGUACAAGUACCGCUGUAAUCAGUGUAGCCUGGCCUUCAAGACCAUUGAAAAGUUGCAGCUCCAUUCUCAGUACCAUGUGAUCAGAGCUGCCACCAUGUGCUGUCUUUGUCAGCGCAGUUUCCGAACUUUCCAGGCUCUGAAGAAGCACCUUGAGACAAGCCACCUGGAGCUGAGUGAGGCUGACAUCCAACAGCUUUAUGGUGGCCUGCUGGCCAAUGGGGACCUCCUGGCAAUGGGAGACCCCACUCUGGCAGAGGACCAUACCAUAAUUGUUGAGGAAGACAAGGAGGAAGAGAGUGACUUGGAAGAUAAACAGAGCCCAACGGGCAGUGACUCUGGGUCAGUACAAGAAGACUCGGGCUCAGAGCCAAAGAGAGCUCUGCCUUUCAGAAAAGGUCCCAAUUUUACUAUGGAAAAGUUCCUAGACCCUUCUCGCCCUUACAAGUGUACCGUCUGCAAGGAAUCUUUCACUCAAAAGAAUAUCCUGCUAGUACACUACAAUUCUGUCUCCCACCUGCAUAAGUUAAAGAGAGCCCUUCAAGAAUCAGCAACCGGUCAGCCAGAACCCACCAGCAGCCCAGACAACAAACCUUUUAAGUGUAACACUUGUAAUGUGGCCUACAGCCAGAGUUCCACUCUGGAGAUCCAUAUGAGGUCUGUGUUACAUCAAACCAAGGCCCGGGCAGCCAAGCUGGAGGCUGCAAGUGGCAGCAGCAAUGGGACUGGGAACAGCAGCAGUAUUUCCUUGAGCUCCUCCACGCCAAGUCCUGUGAGCACCAGUGGCAGUAACACCUUUACCACCUCCAAUCCAAGCAGUGCUGGCAUUGCUCCAAGCUCUAACUUACUAAGCCAAGUGCCCACUGAGAGUGUAGGGAUGCCACCCCUGGGGAAUCCUAUUGGUGCCAACAUUGCUUCCCCUUCAGAGCCCAAAGAGGCCAAUCGGAAGAAACUGGCAGAUAUGAUUGCAUCCAGGCAGCAGCAACAACAGCAGCAGCAACAGCAACAACAACAACAACAACAACAACAACAAGCACAAACGCUGGCCCAGGCCCAGGCUCAAGUUCAAGCUCACCUGCAGCAGGAGCUGCAGCAACAGGCUGCCCUGAUCCAGUCUCAGCUGUUUAACCCCACCCUCCUUCCUCACUUCCCCAUGACAACUGAGACCCUGCUGCAACUACAGCAGCAGCAGCACCUCCUCUUCCCUUUCUACAUCCCCAGUGCUGAGUUCCAGCUUAACCCCGAGGUGAGCUUGCCAGUGACCAGUGGGGCACUGACACUGACUGGGACAGGCCCAGGCCUGCUGGAAGAUCUGAAGGCUCAGGUUCAGGUCCCACAGCAGAGCCAUCAGCAGAUCUUGCCGCAGCAGCAGCAGAACCAACUCUCUAUAGCCCAGAGUCACUCUGCCCUCCUUCAGCCAAGCCAGCACCCCGAAAAGAAGAACAAAUUGGUCAUCAAAGAAAAGGAAAAAGAAAGCCAGAGAGAGAGGGACAGCGCCGAGGGGGGAGAGGGCAACACCGGUCCGAAGGAAACACUGCCAGAUGCCUUGAAGGCCAAAGAGAAGAAAGAGUUGGCACCAGGGGGUGGUUCUGAGCCUUCCAUGCUCCCUCCACGCAUUGCUUCAGAUGCCAGAGGGAACGCCACCAAGGCCCUGCUGGAGAACUUUGGCUUUGAGUUGGUCAUCCAGUAUAAUGAGAACAAGCAGAAGGUGCAGAAAAAGAAUGGGAAGACUGACCAGGGAGAGAACCUGGAAAAGCUCGAGUGUGACUCCUGCGGCAAGUUGUUUUCCAACAUCUUGAUUUUAAAGAGUCAUCAAGAGCACGUUCAUCAGAAUUACUUUCCUUUCAAACAGCUCGAGAGGUUUGCCAAACAGUACAGAGACCACUACGAUAAACUGUACCCACUGAGGCCCCAGACCCCAGAGCCACCACCACCUCCCCCUCCACCCCCUCCACCCCCACUUCCGGCAGCGCCGCCUCAGCCGGCGUCCACACCAGCCAUCCCCGCAUCAGCCCCACCCAUCACCUCACCUACAAUUGCACCGGCCCAGCCAUCAGUGCCGCUCACCCAGCUCUCCAUGCCGAUGGAGCUGCCCAUCUUCUCGCCGCUGAUGAUGCAGACGAUGCCGCUGCAGACCUUGCCGGCUCAGCUACCCCCGCAGCUGGGACCUGUGGAGCCUCUGCCUGCGGACCUGGCCCAACUCUACCAGCAUCAGCUCAAUCCAACCCUGCUCCAGCAGCAGAACAAGAGGCCUCGCACCAGGAUCACAGAUGAUCAGCUCCGAGUCUUGCGGCAAUAUUUUGACAUUAACAACUCCCCCAGUGAAGAGCAAAUAAAAGAGAUGGCAGACAAGUCCGGGUUGCCCCAGAAAGUGAUCAAGCACUGGUUCAGGAACACUCUCUUCAAAGAGAGGCAGCGUAACAAGGACUCCCCUUACAACUUCAGUAAUCCUCCUAUCACCAGCCUGGAGGAGCUCAAGAUUGACUCCCGGCCCCCUUCGCCGGAACCUCCAAAGCAGGAGUACUGGGGAAGCAAGAGGUCUUCAAGAACAAGGUUUACGGACUACCAGCUGAGGGUCUUACAGGACUUCUUCGAUGCCAAUGCUUACCCAAAGGAUGAUGAAUUUGAGCAACUCUCUAAUUUACUGAACCUUCCAACCCGAGUGAUAGUGGUGUGGUUUCAGAAUGCCCGACAGAAGGCCAGGAAGAAUUAUGAGAAUCAGGGAGAGGGCAAAGAUGGAGAGCGGCGUGAGCUUACAAAUGAUAGAUACAUUCGAACAAGCAACUUGAACUACCAGUGCAAAAAAUGUAGCCUGGUGUUUCAGCGCAUCUUUGAUCUCAUCAAGCACCAGAAGAAGCUGUGUUACAAGGAUGAGGAUGAGGAGGGGCAGGACGACAGCCAAAAUGAGGAUUCCAUGGAUGCCAUGGAAAUCCUGACGCCUACCAGCUCAUCCUGCAGUACCCCGAUGCCCUCACAGGCUUACAGCGCCCCAGCACCAUCAGCCAAUAAUACAGCUUCCUCCGCUUUCUUGCAGCUUACAGCGGAGGCUGAGGAACUGGCCACCUUCAAUUCAAAAACAGAGGCAGGCGAUGAGAAACCAAAGCUGGCGGAAGCUCCCAGUGCACAGCCAAACCAAACCCAAGAAAAGCAAGGACAACCAAAGCCAGAGCUGCAGCAGCAAGAGCAGCCCGAGCAGAAGACCAACACUCCCCAGCAGAAGCUCCCCCAGCUGGUGUCCCUGCCUUCGUUGCCACAGCCUCCUCCACAAGCGCCCCCUCCACAGUGCCCCUUACCCCAGUCGAGCCCCAGUCCUUCCCAGCUCUCCCACCUGCCCCUCAAGCCCCUCCACACAUCAACUCCUCAACAGCUCGCAAACCUACCUCCUCAGCUAAUCCCCUACCAGUGUGACCAGUGUAAGUUGGCAUUUCCGUCAUUUGAGCACUGGCAGGAGCAUCAGCAGCUCCACUUCCUGAGCGCGCAGAACCAGUUCAUCCACCCCCAGUUUUUGGACAGGUCCCUGGAUAUGCCUUUCAUGCUCUUUGAUCCCAGUAACCCACUCCUGGCCAGCCAGCUGCUCUCUGGGGCCAUACCUCAGAUUCCAGCAAGCUCAGCCACUUCUCCUUCAACUCCAACCUCCACAAUGAACACUCUCAAGAGGAAGCUGGAGGAAAAGGCCAGUGCAAGCCCUGGCGAAAACGACAGUGGGACAGGAGGAGAAGAGCCUCAGAGAGACAAGCGUUUGAGAACAACCAUCACACCGGAACAACUAGAAAUUCUCUACCAGAAGUAUCUACUGGAUUCCAAUCCGACUCGAAAGAUGUUGGAUCACAUUGCACACGAGGUGGGCUUGAAGAAACGUGUGGUACAAGUCUGGUUUCAGAACACCCGAGCUCGGGAAAGGAAAGGACAGUUCCGGGCUGUAGGCCCAGCGCAGGCCCACAGGAGAUGCCCUUUUUGCAGAGCGCUCUUCAAAGCCAAGACUGCUCUUGAGGCUCAUAUCCGGUCCCGUCACUGGCAUGAAGCCAAGAGAGCUGGCUACAACCUAACUCUGUCUGCGAUGCUCUUAGACUGUGAUGGGGGACUCCAGAUGAAAGGAGAUAUUUUUGACGGAACUAGCUUUUCCCACCUACCCCCAAGCAGUAGUGAUGGUCAGGGUGUCCCCCUCUCACCUGUGAGUAAAACCAUGGAAUUGUCACCCAGAACUCUUCUAAGCCCUUCCUCCAUUAAGGUGGAAGGGAUUGAAGACUUUGAAAGCCCCUCCAUGUCCUCAGUUAAUCUAAACUUUGACCAAACUAAGCUGGACAACGAUGACUGUUCCUCUGUCAACACAGCAAUCACAGAUACCACAACUGGAGACGAGGGCAACGCAGAUAACGACAGUGCAACGGGAAUAGCAACUGAAACCAAAUCCUCUUCUGCACCCAACGAAGGGUUGACCAAAGCGGCCAUGAUGGCAAUGUCUGAGUAUGAAGAUCGGUUGUCAUCUGGUCUGGUCAGCCCGGCCCCGAGCUUUUAUAGCAAGGAAUAUGACAAUGAAGGUACAGUGGACUACAGUGAAACCUCAAGCCUUGCAGAUCCCUGCUCCCCGAGUCCUGGUGCGAGUGGAUCUGCAGGCAAAUCUGGUGACAGCGGAGAUCGGCCUGGGCAGAAACGUUUUCGCACUCAAAUGACCAAUCUGCAGCUGAAGGUCCUCAAGUCAUGCUUUAAUGACUACAGGACACCCACUAUGCUAGAAUGUGAGGUCCUGGGCAAUGACAUUGGACUGCCAAAGAGAGUCGUUCAGGUCUGGUUCCAGAAUGCCCGGGCAAAAGAAAAGAAGUCCAAGUUAAGCAUGGCCAAGCAUUUUGGUAUAAACCAAACGAGUUAUGAGGGACCCAAAACAGAGUGCACUUUGUGUGGCAUCAAGUACAGCGCUCGGCUGUCUGUACGUGACCAUAUCUUUUCCCAACAGCAUAUCUCCAAAGUUAAAGACACCAUUGGAAGCCAGCUGGACAAGGAGAAAGAAUACUUUGACCCAGCCACCGUACGUCAGUUGAUGGCUCAACAAGAGUUGGACCGGAUUAAAAAGGCCAACGAGGUCCUUGGACUGGCAGCUCAGCAGCAAGGGAUGUUUGACAACACCCCUCUUCAGGCCCUUAACCUUCCUACAGCAUAUCCAGCGCUCCAGGGCAUUCCUCCUGUGUUGCUCCCGGGCCUCAACAGCCCCUCCUUGCCAGGCUUUACUCCAUCCAACACAGCUUUAACGUCUCCUAAGCCGAACUUGAUGGGUCUGCCCAGCACAACUGUUCCUUCCCCUGGCCUCCCCACUUCUGGAUUACCAAAUAAACCGUCCUCAGCGUCGCUGAGCUCCCCAACCCCAGCACAAGCCACGAUGGCGAUGGGCCCUCAGCAACCCCCCCAGCAGCAGCAGCAGCAGCAGCAACCACAGGUGCAGCAGCCUCCCCCGCCGCCAGCAGCCCAGCCGCCACCCACACCACAGCUCCCACUGCAACAGCAGCAGCAACGCAAGGACAAAGACAGUGAGAAAGUAAAGGAGAAGGAAAAGGCACACAAAGGGAAAGGGGAACCCCUGCCUGUCCCCAAGAAGGAGAAAGGAGAGGCCCCCACGGCAACUGCAGCCACGAUCUCAGCCCCGCUGCCCACCAUGGAGUAUGCGGUAGACCCUGCACAGCUGCAGGCCCUGCAGGCCGCGUUGACUUCGGACCCCACAGCAUUGCUCACAAGCCAGUUCCUUCCUUACUUUGUACCAGGCUUUUCUCCUUAUUAUGCUCCCCAGAUCCCUGGCGCCCUGCAGAGCGGGUACCUGCAGCCUAUGUAUGGCAUGGAAGGCCUGUUCCCCUACAGCCCUGCACUGUCGCAGGCCCUGAUGGGGCUGUCCCCAGGCUCCCUACUGCAGCAGUACCAGCAAUACCAGCAGAGUCUGCAGGAGGCAAUUCAGCAGCAGCAGCAGCGGCAACUACAGCAGCAGCAGCAGCAAAAAGUGCAGCAGCAGCAGCCCAAAGCAAGCCAAACCCCAGUCCCCCCCGGGGCUCCUUCCCCAGACAAAGACCCUGCCAAAGAAUCCCCCAAACCAGAAGAACAGAAAAACACCCCCCGUGAGGUGUCCCCCCUCCUGCCGAAACUCCCUGAAGAGCCAGAAGCAGAAAGCAAAAGUGCGGACUCCCUCUACGACCCCUUCAUUGUUCCAAAGGUGCAGUACAAGUUGGUCUGCCGCAAGUGCCAGGCGGGCUUCAGCGACGAGGAGGCAGCGAGGAGCCACCUGAAGUCCCUCUGCUUCUUCGGCCAGUCUGUGGUGAACCUGCAAGAGAUGGUGCUUCACGUCCCCACCGGCGGCGGCGGCGGUGGCAGUGGCGGCGGCGGCGGCGGUGGCGGCGGCGGCGGCGGCGGCGGCUCGUACCACUGCCUGGCGUGCGAGAGCGCGCUCUGUGGGGAGGAAGCUCUGAGUCAACAUCUCGAGUCGGCCUUGCACAAACACAGAACAAUCACGAGAGCAGCAAGAAACGCCAAAGAGCACCCUAGUUUAUUACCUCACUCUGCCUGCUUCCCCGAUCCUAGCACCGCAUCUACCUCGCAGUCUGCCGCUCACUCAAACGACAGCCCCCCUCCCCCGUCGGCCGCCGCCCCCUCCUCCGCUUCCCCCCACGCCUCCAGGAAGUCUUGGCCGCAAGUGGUCUCCCGGGCUUCGGCAGCGAAGCCCCCUUCUUUUCCUCCUCUCUCCUCAUCUUCAACGGUUACCUCAAGUUCAUGCAGCACCUCAGGGGUUCAGCCCUCGAUGCCAACAGACGACUAUUCGGAGGAGUCUGACACGGAUCUCAGCCAAAAGUCCGACGGACCGGCGAGCCCGGUGGAGGGUCCCAAAGACCCCAGCUGCCCCAAGGACAGUGGUCUGACCAGUGUAGGAACGGACACCUUCAGAUUGUAAGCUUUGAAGAUGAACAAUACAAACAAAUGAAUUUAAAUACAAAAAUUAAUAACAAACCAAUUUCAAAAAUAGACUAACUGCAAUUCCAAAGCUUCUAACCAAAAAACAAAAAAAAAAAAAAAAAGAAAAAAAAGAAAAAGCGUGGGUUGUUUUCCCAUAUACCUAUCUAUGCCGGUGAUUUUACAUUCUUGUCUUUUUCUUUUCUUUUAAUAUUAAAAAAAAAAAAAAAGCCCUAACCCUGUUACAUUGUGUCCUUUUGAAGGUACUAUUGGUCUGGGAAACAGAAGUCCGCAGGGCCUCCCUAAUGUCUUUGGAGCUUAAACCCCUUGUAUAUUUGCCCCUUUUCAAUAAACGCCCCACGCUGAUAGCACAGAGGAGCCCGGCAUGCACUGUAUGGGAAAGCAGUCCACCUUGUUACAGUUUUAAAUUUCUUGCUAUCUUAGCAUUCAGAUACCAAUGGCUUGCUAAAAGAAAAAAAGAAAUGUAAUGUCUUUUUAUUCUCAGGUCAAUCGCUCACACUUUGUUUUCAGAAUCAUUGUUUUAUAUAUUAUUGUUUUUUCAGUUUUUUUUUUUUUUUUUGUUCCAGAAAAGAUUUUUUGUUUUGUUAACUUAAAAAUGGGCAGAAAGUAUUCAAGAAAAACAAUGUGAACUGCUUUAGCUUUCUGGGGAUUUUUAAGGAUAGCUUUUCUGCUGAAGCCAAUUUCAAGGGGAAAAGUUAAGCACUCCCACUUUCAAAAAAAAAAAAAAAUAAUAACCCACACACACAAAGAGUGUUGAGGACUUGUAGCUUAAAAAAAAUAAGUUUUAAAAACUGACUUUCUGUAUUUAUGAUAGAUAUGACCAUUUUUGGUGUUGAGUAGAUUGUUGCAUUGGAAAUGAACUGAAGCAGUAUGGUAGAUUUAAAAGGAAAAAAAAAAAAAAACCUUUUGUGUACAUUUAGCUUUUUGUAUGGUCCAGCUGACAGCUCCUCAUUUGAUGUUGUCUUGUUCAUUCCUAGCAGAUGAUAGAUUGCAAUCCGUUGAUUCGCCUAAGCUUUUCUCCCCUUGUCCCUUAAUUCCACUUUCUCUUUCUUGUCCCUUAAUUCCACUUUCUCUUUCCUUCUCCCACCUCCCGUCCUAUAAUCUCCCACUUAAGGUAGCUGCCUUCAUUUCUUAGAGGGAGCUGCAGAAUUAUUUUAUAAAACUAAAGAAAGAAUUUCAAGGGAUUCUAGGGGUCAUUAGGAUCCUCACAGAUUAUUUUUGGUUGGGGAGUUGAAACUUUUUAAAGGCAUAUAAUUCUAGUUACCUGUGUCUGUUAGCUUUGUGCAUUUAUUUUUUAUUUAUCCUUCUUUUGGCUUUUUUUUCUUUGUACCCCUUCUUUUCCUCCUUGUUUGGUAGGAGCUUCAAAUAUUCUUUUUUUUUCUAUACUAAAGGAUUUGUUUCCAUUUGUGUAAUUGGCUGUGUACUUUUCUUUUCUAAAAAAAGUUUUUGGUUAGGGAUUUGGUUUUUGGUUUUGUGUUUGUUUUUUCUUUCCUCUCUCAGAAAAAAAAAUUUCAUGCUUUAAAUAAAAUCCAAAGACACACCCUUUCACUGCUGAUGCAGAAAAAAGGGAAAGGGUUCUUGUUACUUGAGAAUUUGUUUCUGAUUUAAACAAACAAGACUUAGUUUAAUAAAAGAAAGAGAAAAACAAAAGAUUCCCAGGUUGUUAUGUGCUUCUUCUGCAAGCAGAGAGGCAAAUGUUAAUGACAAUUCCAUAUACCAAAAGACACAUUUUUUACUUCAAAGUUUUGUCCUUGUGUUAGGCAGUCUGAGCAGCGAGUGAUCCAGAGCGCAGCCAACAAAGCAGCAGAUAGCAGUGUACAGAAAGCAAAAAAGGAACUGUAUGUGAGGCACUUGUUUCUGUUAAUAUCCAUAUUCCUGUUAACACACACCCUUUCUCAUGUAAAAAGAAAAAUAAAUAAAUGGUCUGAACUUUGAAAACUUUGUGCUGCUAAAACAUAGAUUUUGGAGACAAAUAAAUAGAUGCUUUGCUGUUUCACUUUCAUAGCUAAACAUCAACAGAAACCAUCUCCCCUUGCCCCCAAAGUGUGAAAUCCUUCUUCCCUUCGUUUUCUUCCUUAUGUUUCAAAAGGGAACUUUGAAGACUGUGAAUACAGGUUCCAUUGGUCACCUUUCGGGCUUCUUUCCCCAGUGCUGAAGCCACUCAUCGACUUUGCAAAAGACUGGAGCAUUCCAAGAUCUGAAAAUGGAUUUUUUUUCUUUUUUUCUUUUUUAGCCGGGACUAUUUUAUUUUUAUGAAUUUGUUUUUAGUUUAAUGAAAUAGUAGAUCCUGAAAUGUUGUACAUAUUUCUAACUAGGCUGAUGCACAGUGCAAAUUCCUUUUUUAAUUGUUUUUUUUAAGUAGAAAUACUAAAGAAAGAAUACCAUCUAACUAUUCAUACCAGUAUCCAGUUGUAGCAUAAGGUGUCAAAAGCAAGUACGCAAAACAUUUACUGUUUUAACAAGCUAUUUCCUUUUAACAAGAAAUCUUGUAUUUCUUCCUGUGUUUGAGAUGAACAUUUUUAAAUUUUAAAGUUGUACAGUUUUUUGUUUUCCAUUAUUUUAUCUUGUUUGUAACUCUAUGAAAUAUAUAUAUAUAUAUUUUUUGCCAUUUAACUGUUGUAUGUUACUCUGUGUCUGUACCAUAUAGAAAAAAAAUUGUUUUUGUUUUUGGUUCUCUAUGUGAUAUCAGUUAACAAUGUAACACUAGCUUUACCUGUCAAAUUCUGCUAGGUCUUCUCUGAAAACGUUGUUUUUAAAAAUGAUAUUGCUUGGUAAUAGUGCAAUUUCUAUCCUUUUCCCUCCCCCCUCAACUUUUAAGUUCUUUUCUUUAUAAUUUUGCUGCCCCCUCCCUGAUGGUUUGGGUUUUUGUUUUUGUUUUUGUUUUUUUUUUUCAUGGAGCUACUAUGCCAUCCUCCCUCUGUGAGGCAGAGUGACUGUCAGUGUUUUGUUAUGCCAUGCCUUGAGCUGUGGGUGUUUGGCGACAAUAAGGUGGUUGAAUAGAUUGGCUGAGCACACUUCCACCCACCUAGUGUUCUCAGAGGGGUUAUGUGAUUGUUUCAACCUGGAGUGGGUUGCACCCUUAAUGCUUUCCUCUGCAACUAAACCGCCCACAUAUAUGUUCAUUGAAAAAAGUAAGAAUAAUUCUCAGCACUAACCCAGAAGUAGCAAAGCAGUCAGUGAUGGUGAACAUUAGAGGUCAAACAUGAGUUAGAUGUUUGUGGGCUGACAGCCAUCGUGGCUAUGACCAGUACUAUUUACAAAGCAUGAAUUCACUACAAUGCUCAACUGUUUGUUUAGCUUUAUCUCACUUGGGGAAUUUAUUCCUGUCUGCUGCAUUGUAGGUAGCUGGGUAGGAUAUAUUUCCACUUGCUUUUUAAAUUAGUUCUUCACCUCCAUUGACACUCGUUUUUUGGUUUUCUCCCUAUAGUGUGGGUUGGUGCUAGACACCAGUCUGACCCACAGAAUGGGAGUUAUUUCAUCCAUCUUUCCUCCAUCCUUCCAAAAACCACAUAUCUACACAAGGAAAAAUUUAAUACAUCUAGGAAUUUUUUUUUUAAUUACAAGCUAUUUAAAGAGAUGAAUGUGGCCAAAGUUUUACACAAUUGAAAAUAAAGUAAAACAGACGGCAUGUGUUUAAACCUGAGUUUAUCAGGCAUGGCAGGAAGUUGCAGGAGAGAGAGGCAGUGACCCAAGCCAGUGCACUUGAUGUUCAUGGACAUAUAUUUUUUUUAAAUAAUAAAUUAAAACAUUUUAAAUAGAAGCAUAAAUUGAGUUGUUUGUUGGCGCUGAGAUACUGCCCACUGUGAAACAAAGCUUUGACUAGUUUUUUGUUUGUUUACUUUCUUCAGGGGGGAGGGGGGCAAGUUUGGGUAGGAAAGAAAGCAUAAAUGAACGUGACCCUGAGGUGAAGAGGUAUAUGAACAGCCUUUGCAAUGUACAAAAAGAAAAAAAAACAAAAAACAACAAAAAAAAUAGAGCAAGUGAAACCAAAAAUGAUGUUCUUGGUGUUUUUCUAUAAUGUAGUCUUGUUAGCUUUUUUGUUACUGUAACAAUGCUGAUCUCGAACUGUACCAAAAUACAUGGAGACUAACAAACAGAACCACAUGGAACUUUCAAACUGAAAAAAAAAUUUGUCACAAAAACUUUGUUGUCAUAGUUAAGUUGAUUGUAGAUGGUAAUUGAAUAUACUCCUUUGAAAAUAUUUCAUCAAGUAUGUUUCCUGCUCAUUGUGAUACAUUAAAAAAAAAAUAUGAGCAAAA